AGACGGGACUAGCCGGGCGCGCGGCUGAGUGCUGCAGAAUCGCUGGGGUGGCAGAGCCGCCAGCGAGGCUGGGGAUGGGGGCGCCGCUGCUCUCUCCCGGCUGGGGAGCCGGGGCUGCCGGCCGGCGCUGGUGGAUGCUGCUGGCGCCCCUGCUGCCGGCGCUGCUGCUGGUGCGGCCCGCGGGGGCCCUGGUGGAGGGGCUCUACUGCGGCACGCGGGACUGCUACGAGGUGCUGGGCGUGAGCCGCUCGGCGGGCAAGGCGGAGAUCGCGCGGGCCUACCGCCAGCUGGCCCGGCGCUACCACCCUGACCGCUACCGGCCCCAGCCCGGAGACGAGGGCCCCGGGCGGACGCCGCAGAGCGCCGAGGAGGCUUUCCUGCUGGUGGCAACCGCCUACGAGACACUCAAGGUCUCUCAGGCAGCUGCAGAGCUUCAACAGUACUGUAUGCAGAAUGCCUGCAAGGAUGCCCUGCUGGUGGGUGUUCCAGCUGGAAGUAACCCCUUCCGGGAGCCUAGAUCCUGUGCUUUACUCUGAAGACUCGAGAGAAGUUUGCUGAGGAAUGCCUUCAAGCACAAAGUGAUGAAUGACUGCCUUCAAGUCUCAAGAAAACACUUUUCCCUAACUUUUAGAGAUAUUUCAGCCCUUUCCUGUGGCCUGGUCCUAUAGCCAAAAUCACAGAUAUUCAUGAGUUUCUACUUGAGUGAGAAAACUGGGUGAAGGAAUAGAAUUUUAAAUAGUAAUAACUGCUUGUUUUUUUUGUGCAAGUACUUUUAUACAUAAGAUAAACAAAAACCUUACCACCAAACAUACCAAAAUGCACCUCUUUCAUAAGUGAGUUACUAAGAUUUCUAUACCUGGAAUAUCAUGUAUGUUUCAUUUACUGGAUGUUUACAUUUUAGGAAGGAAAAUAGUUUUGUUUAUUUAAACAACUGAAUACUUAUAAACUGUUGUUCCUGGAAGUUAUUUAUUCCAUAAAAAAUUUGUUCUUUUGUCAUGAAUUUAUAAUUCCUAAAUGAAGACCAGAAAGUACAAAUUGCUGGGAGGAAGAAUAGGCUUUAUUAAUCAACUGAUGUCUUGAUUUUUCUAAAUGGGAAGAUUGCUUUAUUUUUAACACUAAUUAUGGGAGCAGAUUCUUAGCAAACUUCUUUGGAAAAGUUAAUGUUAUGAUGUGCAUUAGGCUGCCCCAUCGUGUAUAUAAAUGAAGCAGAUUUGAUUUUUGUAUUCUUACGUUUCUCUGCUUUGUAGUUGUGGCUGUACUUAAAGAAAUACAGAAUUUCAUAUAUUUAAAAAUGUUUAAAAUGUGACCCACAGAACAUUGUAAAUGAUUAAAAACUAACAUGAAAAUAUUACAACCUAAAAGAAUUCUUAACUUCACAAGUGUUUUACUUCGACGAUGUGCCUUUGAUUUAAUUUGGGACACUUUUUUAGAAGGAUACAUUAUUCGUGUUUGCAACGGUCUUUGAAGAGCUUGGAAAUAAAAUUUCUGCUUAAUUAA